GGCAGUGCUCAGCAGCAUCCGACAGGAGCCCUGGCAAACAGGACGGAUUUCCAGGACUCUACCAGCUGCCAGACACGGCAGGGAGAGACCCCAGACCUCCUGGGUCCUGGCUGUGGGCCCGGAUUGGGCUCCCAAGUGGCGUUUGACUCACGUGGGGACACUCUUGGAAGAGACGACACCAGGAGCCUGAAUGGGGAACGAUUCUGUCAGCUACGAGUAUGGGGAUUACAGCGACCUCUCGGACCGCCCUGUGGACUGCCUGGAUGGCGCCUGCCUGGCCAUCGACCCGCUGCGCGUGGCCCCGCUCCCACUGUAUGCCGCCAUCUUCCUGGUGGGGGUGCCGGGCAAUGCCAUGGUGGCCUGGGUGGCUGGGAAGGUGGCCCGCCGGAGGGUGGGUGCCACCUGGUUGCUCCACCUGGCCGUGGCGGAUUUGCUGUGCUGUUUGUCUCUGCCCAUCCUGGCAGUGCCCAUUGCCCGUGGAGGCCACUGGCCGUAUGGUGCAGUGGGCUGUCGGGCGCUGCCCUCCAUCAUCCUGCUGACCAUGUAUGCCAGCGUCCUGCUCCUGGCAGCUCUCAGUGCCGACCUCUGCUUCCUGGCUCUCGGGCCUGCCUGGUGGUCUACGGUUCAGCGGGCGUGCGGGGUGCAGGUGGCCUGUGGGGCAGCCUGGACACUGGCCUUGCUGCUCACCGUGCCCUCCGCCAUCUACCGCCGGCUGCACCAGGAGCACUUCCCAGCCCGGCUGCAGUGUGUGGUGGACUACGGCGGCUCCUCCAGCACCGAGAAUGCGGUGACUGCCAUCCGGUUUCUUUUUGGCUUCCUGGGGCCCCUGGUGGCCGUGGCCAGCUGCCACAGUGCCCUCCUGUGCUGGGCAGCCCGACGCUGCCGGCCGCUGGGCACAGCCAUUGUGGUGGGGUUUUUUGUCUGCUGGGCACCCUACCACCUGCUGGGGCUGGUGCUCACUGUGGCGGCCCCGAACUCCGCACUCCUGGCCAGGGCCCUGCGGGCUGAACCCCUCAUCGUGGGCCUUGCCCUCGCUCACAGCUGCCUCAAUCCCAUGCUCUUCCUGUAUUUUGGGAGGGCUCAACUCCGCCGGUCACUGCCAGCUGCCUGUCACUGGGCCCUGAGGGAGUCCCAGGGCCAGGACGAAAGUGUGGACAGCAAGAAAUCCACCAGCCAUGACCUGGUCUCGGAGAUGGAGGUGUAGGCUGGAGAGACAUUGUGGGUGUGUAUCUUCUUAUCUCAUUUCACAAGACUGGCUUCAGGCAUAGCUGGAUCCAGGAGCUCAAUGAUGUCUUCAUUUUAUUCCUUCCUUCAUUCAACAGAUAUCCAUCAUGCACUUGCUAUGUGCAAGGCCUUUUUAGGCACUAGAGAUAUAGCAGUGACCAAAACAGACACAAAUCCUGCCCUCAGGGAGCUGAUAUUCUUCUAGUGGAGGAAGACAGACUAUAAACAAAGAUAUAUAGGGCCAUUUGCGGUGGCUCACGCCUGUAAUUCCAGGGCUUUGGGAGGCUGAGGCAGGUAGAUCACUUGAGGUCAGGACUUCAAGACCAGCCUAGCCAAUAUGGUGAAACCCUGUCUCUACUAAAAAUACAAAAAUUAGCCGGGCAUGGUGGCGCAUGCCUGUAGUCCCAGCUACUUGGGAGGCUGAGGCAGAAGAAUCGUUUUGAACCCGGGAGGCAGAGGUGACAGUGAGCCAAGAUUGAGCCCCUGCACUCCAGCCUGGGCGACAGAGCGAGACUCCGUCUCAAAAAAUAAAUAAAUAAAAGAUUCUAUUUAUUUAUUUAUUUUUUUGAGAUGGAGUCUCGCUCUGUCGCCCAGGCUGGAGUGCAGUGGCACAAUCUCGGCUCACUGCAAGCUCCGCCUCCUGAGUUCACGCCAUUCUCCUGCCUCAGCCUCCUGAGUAGCUGGGACUACAGGCGCCCGCCACCAUGCCCAGCUAAUUUUUGUAUUUUUAGUAGAGAAGGGGUUUCACCUUGUUAGCCAGGAUGGUCUUGAUCUCCUGACCUGGUGAUCCACCCGCCUCAGCCUCCCAAAGUGCUGGGAUUACAGGCGUGAGCCACCGCACCCGGCCAAAAGAUUUUAAUAGGAUCCCUCUGGUUGCUGGUGGAGGUGAGAGUAUGGUGUAGGGGCAGUGAAGAUCCCAGAGAGGAGGCUACUGUAAUGGUCCAAGCAGGAGGUGAUAGCGAUUUGGAUCAGGGUAACAGAGCUGAGGUGGUGAGAGGCUGACAGGUCAUGCAUCUAUUUUGAAGGAAAGGCCAAGUCCAGGCUCCUUAGCUCGGCAUUCAAGGCUUCUCUCCACCACUGGACACACUUACUCUCUAGCUUCUCAGACCCUGUAGCAAUCAGAAUCAUGACCCCCGGUGAUGUCCACAUCUUAAUCCCCUGAACCUGUGAAGAGGUGACCUUCCAUGGCAAAAGGGACUUUGCAGGUGAGAUUAAGUAAAGGAUCUUGAGAAGGGGUGGUUAUCCUGGAUUGUCUGGGUGGGCUCAAUGGAGUCACGAGGGUCCUUUUAAGAGGGAGGCAGGAGGGUCAGGGUCAGUCACAGGAGGUGACAACGGAAGCAGAUGUCAUAGUGACGUGAGGAGGUGCCAAGAAAUGCAGGCAGCUUCCAGAAGCUGAAACAGACAAGGAAACAGAUUCUCUCUGAAGCUCCCAGAAGGAACACAGACCUCCUGACACUUUUAGACCUCUGAUCCGCAGACCUUUAAGAAAAUACAUUUGUAUUGUUUUAAGUCACUAUGUUUGGGGUGAUUUGUUAUAGCAGCCGUGGGAAGCUAAUACACACCCUUCGGGCUAUAUUCACGCUUCUGCAUCUUUCCUGAAGCUGUGCCACUGGCUGGAAUGUCCUUCUGAUCUAUGUUGUGCAGUUCAACAAUCAAGAGCCAUCUGUGGCUAUUCAAAUUCGAAUCAAUUGGCCAGGCCUGGUGGCUCCUGCCUAUAAUCUCAGCACUUUGGGAGGCCGAGGUGGGAGGAUUGCAUGAGCCCAGGAGUUUGAGACCAGCCUGGGCGACAUAGCAAGACCCCAUCUCUACAAAAAAUACAAAAAUUAGCCAGACGUGGUGGGGCGUGCCUGUAGUUCCAGCUACUGAGGAGGGAGUUGCUUGAAUCCUUCUGCUUCAAUCCUCCUUAAAGCAGGUAGAUUGCUUGAGCCCGGGAAGUGGAGUUUGCAGUGAGCUUAGAUCACACCGCUGCACUCCAGCCUGGAUGUCAGAAUGAGACUCCAUCUCAAAAAAAAAAAGAAAGAAAGAAUAAAUUUUCAUUUCAAAUUUAGUUCCUCGGGCACACUGGCCAUAGUUCAAGUGCUCAGUAGCCACAUAUGGCUGGUGACUGCCAUAUUCGACAGCACAGCUAUAGAACAUUGCCAUCAUAACAGAGAUUUCUGUUACAAAAUGCUGUUCUAGAAUUUACUUUUGAACUCUACCUGCUCAGAUCUUUUAAAUUACAUGGUAGGCCAGGCAUGGUGGCUCACGCCUGUGAUCCCAGCACUUUCGGAGGCCCAGUCGGGAGGAUCCCUUGAGCCCAGAAGCUGGAGACCUGCCUGGGCAACAGAGCAAGACCCCAUCUCUACAAAAAUAAAAAAAAGAAAAUUAGCCUGGUUUGGUGGCACAUGCCUGUAGUGCCAGCUACUAGGGAGACUGAAGUGGGAGGAUUGCUUCAGCCUGGGAGGUUGAGGCUGCAGUGAGCCGUGAUCUCAUCACUGCACUCUAGCCUAGGUGACGGAGCGGGACCCUGCCGCUAAAUAAAUAAAUAAAUAAAUAACAUAGUAGUGAUACCUGUGUCUGCGGUCAUUACUCCAGAACAGCACUUCACAUAUAGUUUCUCCUUUAAGGUCAUUCUCACAACAGCCCAGGGAGAUAGGGUGGCAUGCUUCAUUUUAUAAGCUGAGGUCCUGGGAGGGGAGGUCAUUUACCCAAGAUCACACAGCAAGAACACCAGACAGCUGGAAUUUGAUCCCAGUUUUGACUCCAAUGCUCUUGCUCUUCAUCAUCAAUAAUUUCCUUCAAGGCGUCCCUCAAAUGUCACUUCCUCCAGGAAGCCCUCCCUGAUUUAUGCUCCUUCCAGAAAGAAUGGGCUCUUCCUUUCUCUGAGUCUCUGGAACACAAGGUCCCAGCUAAACUGUAAAUUCCCCAAGGGUAACAACUGGACUAAUUUUUUUUAAUUUAAUUUAAUUUUAUUUUUUUGAGAUGAAGUCUUGCUCUGUCACCCAGGCUGGAUUGUAGUGGCACGAUCUCGGCUGACCGCAACCUCCACCUCCCGGGUUCAAGCGAUUCUUAUGCCUCAGCCUCCCGAGUAGCUGGGAUUACAGGCGCUGCCACCACACUUGGCUAAUUUUUGUAUUUUUAGUAGAGACAGGGUUUCACCAUGUUGGCCAGGCUGGUCUCGAACUCCUGACCUCAGGUGAUCCACCCACCUUGGCCUCCCAAAGUGCUGGGAAUACAGGCAUGAGCCACCGUUCCCGGCCUUAUCCUUGACUUAGAAUACCUAACCUCCUGGGAAUGCAGCCCAUAGGUCUCAGCCUUAUUUCACCCAGCUCCUGUUCAAGAUGGAGUCACUCUGGUUCACAUGCCUCUGACAUUUCCCCGCUCCCUUUUAUAAGAGAACCUUUAAUCCUAAGGGUUGUAGAGGGAGGAAGAUACAACUUCUGUGACUUCUUCAGGCUGGACAGGGGUGACGAUAUACCUGCCUAACUCUUAGGAUCUAUUGGAUUCAGGGUAGACAGGAGCUCAGUCAGAAAGCACUGGUAUCACUUUUUUUUUUUUUUUUUUUUUUUGAGACGGAGUUUCACUCUUGUUGCCCAGGCUGGAGUGCAAUGGCACGAUCUCAGCUCACCACAGCCUCCGCCUCCCAGGUUCAAGCGAUUCUCCUGCCUCAGCCUCCCCAGUAGCUGGGACUACAGGCGUGUGCCACCAAACCCAGCUAAUGUUUUUUUUUUUUUAUUUUUAGUAGAGACGGGGUUUCUCCAUGUUGGCCAGGCUGGUCUCGAACUCCCGACCUCAGGUGAUCCACCCGCCUCGGCCUCCCAAAGUGCUGGGAUUACAGACAUGAGCCACCACGCCCGGCCUGAUAUUUUAUUACUUAGUAUUUUACUCUGAAUUAUCAUGCGUGAAUUAAGACCAAGGCUGUCUUGUAAAAUAAAAUUUGUUGUGGAACAAUUUAUACAGCUCCUUUGAGGUAGGAGGCAGGACUCAACUCUGGAGAUGGGGCUCGGCUCGAAUAUUGGACCAAAUUGAGGACCAGCUAAAACAGGGAGGAGGCUGAAGCAACUUAUUAUUUUUAUUUAUUUUUAUUUUUUGGAGAAGGAGUCUUGCUCUGUUACCCAGGCUGGAGUGCAGUGACACGAUCUCGGCUCACUGCAACCUCCACCUUCCGGAUUCAAGUGAUUCUCCUGCCGCAGCCUCCCGAGUAGCUGGGACUACAGGCGCAUGCCACCAUGCCCAGCUAAUAUUUUUGUAUUUUUUAGUAGAGAUGGGGUUUCGCCAUAUUAGCCAGGCUGGUCUUGAACUCCUGACUCAGGUGAUCUGCCCACCUCGGCCUCCCAAAGUGCUGGGAUUACAGGUGUGGGCCACCACGCCUGGCCCGAAGCAACUUUCUAUGACACGCCUACCAGUGUGCCAUGUCAGUUUGCCAUUGCCAUGGCAACACACCCAGGAGUUACUGCCCCUUCCCAUGGCAAUGACCCCAUGACCCAGAAGUUACUGCCCCUUCCCUAGAUAUUUCUGCAUAAACUGCCCCUUAAUCUACAUGUAAUUAAAAAUAGGUAUAGGCUAUUUUUAUACCUAUAUAAAUAGGUAUAGGCUAAAAAUAGGUAUAGGCUGGGCGUGGUGGCUCAUGUCUGUAAUCCCAGUACUUUGGGAGGCCAAUGCAGGUGGAUCACCUGAGGUCAGGAGAUCAAGACCAUCCUGGCUAACAUAGUGAAACCCUGUCUCUACUAAAAAUACAAAAAAUUAGCCAGGCGUGUUGGCGGGAGCCUGUAGACUCAGCUACUCGGGAGGUUGAGGCAGGAGAAUGGCGUGAACCCAGGAGGCGGAGCUUGCAGUGAGCCGAGAUCACACCACUGCACUCCAGCCUGGGUGACAGAGCAAGACUCCGUCUAAAAAAAAAAAAUAGUAAGAAAGAAGGAAAGACACAAAGACAGAAAGAAGGAAGGAAAGAAAGCAAGCUGUUUUCCCCUGCCUUGCCCCUGCUCACCUUUGAAUUCUUUUCUGGGCAAAGCCAAGAACCCUCGUGGGCUAAAACCCCGCUUUGGGGCUUAAAGUUUGCAAAAUCCUCCCAUUAAUCUAUUGGGACCAGUUGCCACUUAGGAGCAUUCUUUGAUAACUUUUACAAAACAUCUUUUGUGGUUUUUGAAAUGUUUUCAUUUUGUAGAUCAUUAGCCCUUCUUUUUUGAACUGGAAUACAUUUCACGGGAAUUUUCAAAUUUAAGUCUGUGCAAUGUUACAUAAAAUACCUUUGAUUAUUAAAAGCCAUCUGUUUUGCUAUAACUUCCCUUUUUUGUUCUAAAGUUUGUCUAUUUCUGCUAUUUGUUUUUUUACCAUAGAAAUAUUGAUUUCCUUAAGUUUUCAAAGAACCAAGUUAUUAAUAAUUUCUCUAAGAACUAGUCUCAAGCUUGCUAUACAAUCCUAUGGUUGAUAGACUGUGGCUUUCUUGUUGAUUUCCAUUUGUUGUUCAUUUCCUCCAAUUUUCCUUUUUUAAAAAUUAUAAUUAUUGUUUGGAUUAUU